CGCGCCUCGCCAUCCUGUCCCCAGGUCCCUGGCUCGGUCCCGACCGCGGCAAGGGCCAGAACCAGACCUCACCGUCCGGGAUCGCGGACGCCGUCCGGGCUCAGCCCUCUCCCCACCGCCCCCGGAGCUGCAUUGCUUUGUUUAACCUCUGCCAGACCGUUUCGCACAAACUCUUGUUGCCCCAAUUCUGAUGAGCCACCAGUUUGAUAGCUGAGGCAAGACAAAGGUUUCCCCUGUUUACCAAGGGCCGGGGCCAGGAGACUGCGCGCUGCCCGUGGUGUAAAAUCUGUUUUCUUUAUCUUCGCCCGGGGCUUGUUGCGAUGGUUUUCCUGGCACUAUAACCGUCCUUUCUUGCAGAGCUCUGUAGUGGCGAGAUUGGACCUCCUAACCCUACGGAUACGCUUACAAGAGCAGUGAUUCCCAGGCUUUCUCAGCAAUGUACCCCAUUUCCUGACAUUUACAGCUGAAGGUGAAGUUUCCCUUUUGCAAGGAGAAAAUUUUGGUGGAGAAUUAUCCAACAAGAAAAAGACCUGUGGCUAUUAAGAUAGUGACGUUUAACAAAGUCAUGGCCAUGGAGGAAAGUAAACUUACAAAGAAUGUCCAUAAUGAGGCUGUGAGUGCUGAUGUUUCAGACAAGAAGAAGGGAGGCAAAUUCCAGCCUUUUAAAAAGUUGUUUGGCAAAAGGAAAAAGAAAGACCCUUCGUUGUUCCGGGUGCCGUCGUUGGGGAAGAAGAGUUACUCUCACCAGAGUGUCAGCAAUGGGACCUUCUCUUCGGAUGAGGAGACCCUGGAAGACAAUCUAAGGUCCUUCAACUAUUCUAUGGGAACCCGGGCAUUUUCCCAUGACAGUAUUUUUAUCCCUGAUGGGGGAGCAGAAAGUGAGCAGACAGUUCAAGCAAUGUCACAGGACAACAUCCUGGGCAAAGUCAAAACUCUUCAGCAACAGUUGGGCAAGAAUAUCAAGUUUGGGCAGCGGUCACCCAAUGCCAUUCCCAUGAAUAAGGCAAACAGUGGAGAGGCUAGCUUAGAAGAGGAUCUGUUCCUGACCAGUCCCAUGGAAAUUGUGACUCAGCAGGACAUCGUCCUCUCAGACGCAGAGAACAAGUCCAGUGAUACGCCAAGUUCUCUAAGUCCUCUGAAUCUCCCUGGAGCUGGAAGUGAGAUGGAAGAGAAGGUUGCUCCCGUUAAACCGUCUCGGCCAAAAAGGCACUUCUCUUCUGCUGGCACCAUCGAAAGUGUCAACUUAGAUGCCAUCCCCCUGGCCAUCGCUCGCCUGGACAACAGUGCCGCCAAGCACAAGCUGGCUGUUAAGCCAAAAAAACAGAGGGUGUCAAAGAAGCACAGGCGCCUUGCCCAGGAUCCACAACAUGAGCAAGGCGGCCUUGAGAGUCGGCCCUGCCUGGACCAGAACGGACACCCAGGCGAGGACAAGCCAACGUGGCACGAAGAGGAACCCAAUCCGCUGGAUUCCGAGGAAGAGAGAAGACGCCAAGAAGACUACUGGCGAGAACUGGAGGCCAAGUGCAAGCGGCAAAAGGCGGAAGCAGCCGAGAAGAGACGCCUAGAGGAGCAGAGGCUGCAGGCGCUGGAGAGGAGGCUUUGGGAAGAGAACAGAAGGCAGGAGCUCUUGGAGGAGGAGGGCGAGGGGCAGGAGCCGCCUCUAGAGGCGGAAAGGGCGCCGCGGGAAGAGCAGCAGCGGAGCCUGGAAGCGCCAGGUUGGGAGGACGCGGAGCGGAGGGAGCGUGAGGAGCGCGAGCGCCUGGAGGCGGAGGAGGAGCGAAGGCGUCUGCAGGCCCAGGCCCAAGCGGAGGAGAGGCGGCGGCUGGAGGAGGACGCCAGGCUGGAGGAGCGGAGGCGGCAGGAGGAGGAGGAAGGAAGAUGCGCGGAGGAGCUCAAAAGGCAGGAGGAGGAGGAGGCUGAGGGAUGGGAAGAGCUGGAACAGCAGGAGGCGGAGGUGCAGGGGCCGCCCGAGGCGUUGGAGGAGACUGGGGAGGGCCGGCGGGGCGCGGAGGAGGAGGAUCUGGGGGAAGAGGAGGAGGAGGGCCAGGCGCACCUGGAGGACUGGAGGGGGCAGCUCAGUGAGCUUCUGAACGACUUUGAGGAGAGGCUCGAAGACCAGGAACGCCUGAAACCCGAAGGACAAAGAGAACACUCCGAGGAGCCAGGUAUUUGCGAGGAGCAGAACCCAGAGGCCGAGCGGCGAAGAGAGCAGCAGGGAAGGAGCGGGGAUUUCCAGGGGGCCGAUCGUCCUGGGCCCGAGGAAAAGAGAGAAGAAGGGGACACGGAGCCUCUCCUGAAACAAGAGGGGCCGGUGGAAGCCGCGCAGCCUCCGGUGGAGAGGAAAGAAGCCGCCGCCCUUGAACAAGGCCGCAAGGUGGAGGAGCUGCGGUGGCAGGAGGUGGACGAGAGACAGACCAUGCCCCGGCCCUACACGUUCCAGGUGUCCUCCGGAGGGAAGCAGAUUCUCUUUCCCAAAGUCAACCUGAGCCCCGUGACGCCCGCAAAGGACACGGGGCUCACCGCUGCUCCCCAGGAACCAAAGGCCCCCAAAGCCAGCCCAGUCCAGCACGCCCUACCGUCGUCCCUGAGCGUUCCCCACACCGCCAUUCUGGUCACGGGCGCGCAGCUCUGUGGCCCGGCAGUCAACCUGAGCCAGAUCAAGGACACCGCGUGCAAGUCCCUCCUGGGCUUGGAGGAGAAGAAGCACGCGGAAGCCCCAGCUGGGGAGAACCCUCCCCGAGGCCCCGGCGACGCGAGGGCGGGCAGCGGGAAGGCUAAGCCCCGCCAGGAGUCUCCCAGCAGCGCGUCCGCACUCGCAGAAUGGGCUUCCAUUCGGUCCAGAAUCCUGAAGAACGCAGAGAGUGACCCGCGCAGCAGCGAGAGGGACCAGUUGAGGCCCGGUGAUGAGUCCACUCCCAGGGGCCGGUGUGAUUCCCGCGGGAACCAACGGAAGACUCCGCCAGUCAAUGCAAAGUUCUCUAUUAUGCCUGCCUGGCAGAAAUUUUCCGAUGGUGGCACGGAGACCUCCAAACAGAGCACGGAAGCUGAAAGCAUACGAAAAAGACCCAUGCUGGGACCCAGCGAAGAGACAGCCCCCCAGCCUCCUCCUGCUGGUGUUCGCGAGCUCGGGAAGGGUCCGGAGAAGUCGGAGAUGCACCGGGAGCCCGCAGACACCACCGAGGGAUGCAAAUUUGCCAAAGACCUCCCGUCUUUCCUUGUCCCAAGCCUUCCUUACCCUCCGCAGAAAGUGGUGGCCCACACAGAGUUCACGACCUCGUCGGACAGCGAGACUGCAAACGGGAUAGCAAAGCCAGACCCUGUGAUGCCAGGUGGAGAGGAAAAAGCCUCACCGUUUGGAAUAAAAUUGAGAAGGACCAACUAUUCCUUGCGCUUCAACUGCGACCAACAGGCAGAACAGAAGAAGAAGAAGAGGCACAGCAGCACCGGAGACAGCGCGGAUGCAGGGCCGCCUGCAGCGGGGAGCGCUCGUGGAGAGAAAGAGAUGGAGGGUGUGGCCCUCAAGCAUGGUCCAUCCCUCCCCCAAGAGCGGAAGCAAGCCCCUUCCACCCGGAGGGACUCCGCUGAACCUUCCAGCAGCCGCUCUGUUCCUGUGGCCCACCCUGGGCCUCCACCGGCCAGCAGCCAGACCCCGGCUCCGGAGCACGACAAGGCAGCAAACAAAAUGCCACUGGCACAAAAGCCAGCACUGGCUCCCAAGCCCACCAGUCAGACCCCACCAGCAUCCCCACUUUCCAAACUGAGCAGGCCCUACUUGGUAGAGCUGCUGUCUCGCCGAGCGGGGAGGCCGGACCCAGAGCCAAGUGAGCCGUCCAAGGAGGACCAGGAGAGCAGUGACCGCCGGCCACCCUCGCCCCCAGGCCCCGAGGAAAGGAAGGGACAGAAGAGGGACGAGGAGGAAGAGGCGACAGAGAGGAAACCUGCUUCCCCACCUCUGCCUGCCACUCAGCAAGAGAAACCUUCUCAAACACCCGAGGCCGGGAGGAAAGAGAAGCCGAUGCUUCAGAGCAGACACUCCUUAGAUGGCUCCAAACUUACAGAGAAAGUGGAAACUGCUCAGCCGCUGUGGAUAACGUUAGCACUGCAAAAGCAAAAGGGGUUUCGGGAGCAGCAGGCGACGCGGGAGGAGAGAAAGCAAGCCAGAGAGGCCAAACAGGCAGAAAAGCUCUCCAAAGAAAAUGUCAGUGUCAGCGUGCAGCCUGGAAGCAGCAGUGUCAGCAGAGCAGGUUCCCUGCACAAGUCCACUGCUCUGCCAGAAGAGAAGAGGCCCGAGACUGCAGUGUCCAGGCUUGAGCGCAGAGAACAGCUGAAAAAGGCCAAUACUCUUCCUACGUCUGUGACAGUGGAGAUCUCCGACUCGGCUCCCCCAGCGCCGCUGGUAAAAGAAGUCACCAAGAGGUUUUCCACCCCGGAUGCUGCCCCCGUGUCAACAGAACCAGCCUGGCUGGCUUUGGCCAAAAGGAAAGCAAAGGCUUGGAGCGACUGUCCACAGAUUAUUAAGUAAAGAGUGACUCUCACCCAUCCCUACUGCCAGUUAUUGGCUCCUCUCUUGCCCUUUUUAUUUAUUUAUUUUUUAUAUGGGGUAAAGAAAUCAAGCUAGGGAAAAGAAGCAUGUUUUAUAGGCUCCAAAAUAAUGUUUAGAAACUGAACUGGUGGUGUUCAUUGUAAAGAGUGGAUUUGCACAACCCUAGGUCCUGGUGCCUCGAGCUCCUCCUAGUUCUCAAGAGAAAAUUCCGUCCACAGGACCACAUGAAGCAAAAUCUCUAAGCUAAGAACUCGUGAGAGCCUGCCAUGCCCAUUUCAUGGCCUUGCACACACACCCACCCACACACCAUUCAGAACAUGUACUUUUGCCAACCUUUGGUAAUGGUUUUUUGAUUCUAUGCACUAAUUUUCUUUGUCCAAAACAUUUACUCUACCAUAUGUCUGGGAAUGUUUAUCCUUUCUACAGUAAUGGUGAAAGGAUCAUAUCUAGCUAAAAGCAAGAACACCCAUUCUCCUGAAUGCAGUGAGUAAUUGGGAAUCACAAGGAACAUUCUGGCACCCAACUGUGCCCAUCUUAGUUUUCAUGAGUUUUCCCCACUCUGAAGCUGUAACCCAGAAGGCACAUCCAUUCACAUUUUUACCGCACUGUGGAUUCAUAGUGUGGGGCCCUGUUAUUCCAAUACCCUCCUUAAGGACAUGUGAAGCAUUUGGCCCAGUUGGCUCCCAGGGAACAUUUUAAUUUAAUGUAGUGAAGAAAGACAAUUCUAGAUCAGAGCUACAAGUUCACUUUCUGUCUCUGAGAAUCUCCAUCUAGGGCAGUAGUUCUUAUGAUGUGUAGGCUCCCUCCUAGGGCCUACUCAAUCAGAGCCUGUGGGGACUGGGCCAGGAAUAUGUAUUCUGGCAAAAACUCUUCAGGUCAGUUCUGAUAGAUCCCAAAGGUUAAGAACUGUGAGAAACACUGAUCCUAAUGCAAUCUAAUUUUUCAGACUUCGAAGGGGAGGCUCAUUCACUCAAAAAGCAACAGUGAGACAGGAAAAAUAAUAAAACAACCCCCCAAGCCAGCCAUUUAUUACAAGAAGCAACAGGUUAUUGACAUUACAUGUUUGAAAAUUCCCUUUGGUCUUUAGGGAAAAUAAACAGGAAGCCAAGAUUUGGAGCCUUUGUAAUAAGGACUUCCUGCAGAAAGUCUUUUCUUUACUAUAAUUGAGUAAUUCAUAUUUAGAGUCACAUGUCCAGUAGCAUUUCUAAUUUUGAGCAUUCACCUUGCUACCUUUAAAAAACAUCUGAGUUUUAAGUGGCCUUUUUAUCAUCAUACACAUGUGCAUACAAAGAAGGGACUUGGCAGUUUAAAAGCCACAUAUAUUCACUUUUAUUGCCCUAAAUUUACAUGAAACAGACAUACUGGCAAACUCACAUAUUGCUGGUGCUAACCUUAUAUUUCAUAGUGUUGGCAUAUUCCCCUUUUCUUAGAUUCUUACUCCGAAAUAUAGGUACACAUCCUUUGCUCUGUGCAGAGGGAAUUACAUCCUUUUUCCUCUCCUACAAAAACAUGCUUUAUUAAGUAUCCAUCAUUACUUUCCUUUAUGCUCGCUCAAUAUGCAAUGUGCUGUUAUUCUACCAUGUACCUUAAAUAAAGGAUGAUGGCAAAGUUAUUUACCAUGUAGAAACCAUUUUCUUUCUAGAAACAAUAGCUCAGCCUCACUGUAGCAGCUGGCAUGUGUGGUCAAGUGGAUAGUUGUACUCUUGCAAGUUGGAUUUAAUAUCAUAUAUACUGGACCUUCAGACUGUUAAAAAUCAAUGUAACCUUUUUUUAUUGCUAUGGCAAGCAAUUAGUAUUUCACUGCACGUCUUCCAUACUAAUGUUCAUUUCUAAAUCUUAUAUGUAGGCAUUUGUUAGUUCCAAUGAUUUCCUCACUAAUAUAACACUUUUUAAUGGGAAUCUUUCCACCUACAGCCCUGGAAUGAUAAUGCUACAGUAAUUCUUCUGAAUUGACUUUUUCUUUCAUCCUGUCAGCUUUGGACAAUAUCCCAAUUAUGGCAGGGAACAGGUGGGGAACUAAGAUCAGUUACAAAAAGUUGUAGAUGUGUCAACUUUGUAUUGGCUGGGAUAUCACUGUGCCCAAACAAAACAGGCGAAAUACCUCAGUUAAAAUUUUUCCAUCAAAGUCUUUAAAAGAAGAGUAUACUGAAGAAAGGGCAGUCACAAUACUUACUUCUAACAGCUUCUAAAGGGUACAUGUUUAACAUUUCAUUUCAAAAUCACCCCAAAUUUGCACUAAAUACCAAUGAAGUGUUAUUUUGCUUUAGUAGUCUUCUGAGCAACAAACUAUGGGGAAUUCUGUAAAAACAUAUAAAAAGUUCAAGACUUUUUUUUUAAAUGAAUGAUCACUAUGUUAAAUGCAAACUUUUUUUUUUUUUUAUUUAAACAAACAUACACUUCUCCUGGCAAGGUUAUAGAUGAUUAACCUCUGUUCAUAGACUUAUAUAUAAAACUAGAGGGUUUUUUGUUUACUUUUUUAAUUUUUCAAGUGCAAUUGUUUCUUACACAGACAUUAUUACUAUUAAAUUAUCAUUUAGCCAGUUAUCUGCAAAUAUAUAGUAUGUAUUGUCUCUUCUUGUGACGUUUAGUUUAAUUGCUUAUUUUAAAGCAGAAACAUUAGUUACAAGUGUCUUACAAUAUUUUUACCAACAGUAAAGUAGAGACUUAAUGAAAAUACCUUAGUGUGAUUUUAAUAUAAUUUGCAUAUUUUAGUUGUAUAAAGUUUUAAUGUAAAAUGUCCAUUAUUGAAGGGAAAAGAUCUUUCAAUAAAAAAUACCCACGAGA